UGGAGCUGUCACCCUCUGAGUUGCCACAGCAACUGCUUCCCAUGUGGCUGGUCACUGGAACAGCCUGUUGGACAGAUAGGGUGGCUUCCUUCUACACAUACUUGCACUGACCACUAGACUGGCCUUUGGGUGGAGCUGGACUAUGGCCAGUGCCAGGGUGACUUUAACCACAGUAGAACAAUCAAAUCAGUUCGUUGCUCCUCAAAAUAAGUGUCUCUCACUAUCCUGUCUCAUGUGUUGAGGAGAGUGACACUAAUCAGAGUGAACGUUUUGCUGUGGCCCUUAGUCCUUAGCACAUCACAUAAAUUAACUCCGUUCUUUCUCAUGGUGACUCGGAAAUGAGUACUGUUUUCAUACCCAUUACACAAAAAAAGAAAACUGAGAAAAUGUUAAUCGAAGUCACACAGUCAAAAGUGUCAGACAAACCCACAUUGAGAGAUAUUCCAUGAAAUGACUGGCCUGUACUCUUCAAAAAUGCCAUUGUCUUGAAACACAAAAGAAACGUUUAGGAAUUCUUCCAGAUGUAAGUAGACUAAACUUGACAACUGAAUGCGAUGCAGGGCCCAGGAUUUUUCCAUAAAAGAUAUUUUUGAAGAAAUUGGUAAAAUCUGAAUGAGGUCUAUAGAUUAGAUAAUAAUGUUAUGUCAAUGAUAAUUUUCUGAUUUCAAUUAUUAUACUGUGGUUAUGUAAGAGAAUGUCCUUGUUUUCAGCAAAGCAUUUGCAAACCGAAAGUAUUAGGGGGUAUAGAGGCUUCCUGUUUGAAACCAACUCUCAAAUGAUUUAGGGAAAAAAUUAUAGGUAAGUAGGUAGAAGUAGGUAGAAAGAUGGAGGUUAAAUCAAAUGUGGUAAAAUGUUAUAUGUAGGGAAUCUGGGUGAAGGGCUUACAGGAAUUUUUUCUACUAUUCUUGCAAGUGUUCUGAAAGUUUGAAAUUAUGUCAAGAGACAAAAAGUUAAAAGAAAAAGAAAGCAAGUGCCCGAGCAGGGAUGGUAUCCUGGGGUGACUGUUAAUACUAUCAGUUCCUGUUCACUGUGCCCUGGGCACCAGACUCUGUGCUAUGGCCUCAUGUGCAGAAGAACCUCAUUCUAUCCUCACCACAUUCUGAGCGGAAAGACCACUGUGGCUCCCAGUACACACAUGCCAGUCAGAAAGGUGGGGGGAUUUAAUCCAGGCCCCCCAGCUCCUUGGAGCAGUUCCGACUUGAAACUAGGCUCCCUGAUUUCAAGGUCUGAACUCUUAGCCUCAGUCUCACUCUUGACUCUGACCUUUUUGGGAGAGUGGGGAUGGGCAGGACAAAGGCGUUUCUUCCUGGAGUAGUAGCAGAGUGAAGGCCCCGGGACACAAGCUAACAAGAUCCAUUUGCGGGAGGGAGAGGAGCUGUGUUCCAGGAUCCUGCAGGGGGCAGAGCCAGCAGUGCCAAGCAGGAGACACUGGCUUGUGGGAGGGGCUGCAGAUGCCCAGUGGAGUUGCCAGGAGGUGGCCACAGUGGCUUCCAGCAGGGGAGCCACGGGGAAGAGCCUGGAGUGACCUGGAGCUGGGUGAGGUAGACGUUCUGGGCUGGAAGAGUGGCCUUGGAGGAGCUCACUGGGGCGUGCCGAUGCUCUCCGUCCAGCCCAAAGGGAAGCAGAAGGGCUGUGCGGGCUGUAACCGCAAGAUCAAGGACCGCUAUCUGCUGAAGGCAUUGGACAAGUACUGGCACGAAGACUGCCUCAAGUGUGCCUGCUGUGACUGCCGCCUGGGCGAGGUGGGCUCCACCCUCUACACCAAGGCCAACCUCAUCCUGUGCCGACGCGACUACCUGAGGCUCUUUGGCACCACAGGGAACUGUGCUGCUUGCAGCAAGCUGAUCCCAGCCUUCGAGAUGGUGAUGCGGGCCCGGGACAACGUGUAUCACCUCGACUGCUUCGCCUGCCAGCUCUGCAACCAGAGAUUUUGUGUGGGAGACAAAUUCUUCCUGAAGAACAACAUGAUCUUGUGUCAGAUGGACUAUGAGGAAGGGCAGCUCAAUGGCACCUUUGAAUCCCAAGUUCAGUAACGCCCGGCGCCUGGCCUCCAGGCCCGUCUGUCCAUCUGCCCGCCUGCCCACCUGCCUGGCCGGCCAGCCAGCCACUCUACCAGUGCAGGCUGGCCAGCCGCUCUCCUGCCACAUUAGAACUUCUCCGUCCUCGAUGGGAGGGAUGGCCCUUCCUCCUCCACCACCGCCCGUCUGUGUGUGACCCCUCCUGGGGCCAGGCCGGGCCUGUACAGUCUGUCUUCUGUAUAUAAAUGGGAACAUUUAUUUUAUGAGAAAUGUAAUGCGAUUUUAUUACUGGCGUGGAUUAAACUUAUGAAUGUUUCCGGGA